GCUUAGCAGGGGAAAGAUGGCGGUGACGGGCUGGUUGGAGAGUCUGCGGACAGCCCAGAAGACUGCGCUGCUGCAGGACGGGAGAAGGAAGGUUCACUAUUUAUUCCCAGACGGCAAGGAAAUGGCUGAAGAAUAUGACGAGAAGACGAGUGAACUACUUGAAAGGCCUGAGUGUGGACUGAUGGGCAGACAGGAGGACCUCACUUGAGCCACUGGGCCCAGCUCUAGAACAGCAGAUCUUUUUCUUACUCUUCUUCCUAUCCACCACUGCUGCCCUGGCAAAAUACUCUCCAUUAUUAAUUUUUAAGUAUAAAUAAUCCCAGGGGUUGAGCUGGCUUUUGCUUGUGCAUUCUAUGAAGUAAAGUAGGGACAUGGUUUUUGUGGCAAUAAAUAGGAAUAGUUUCCAUUUUUCUAGCUAAGUAUACAAAUUUGAUAAUUAGCCAAACCAGUUUUCUGUUAGAAAAAUUCAAAGUAAUUUACAGAGGAAGAAUUGCCAAUAGGUGUGCGUCAGUCUGGGACAGAGUUCCUCCCGUCGGUGUUAAUAAGCAUGUUAGUGUCCUGUUUUUUUCCUACCCUCUCAGUGCUAUUCAUUCCCACCCCCCACAAUGAUUGCUGCAUGUAUUCAUAGAGGAAAAAACUGAAGGCCCCACAACAAUGAUCGGAACAUCAAACCAGCCUGAGAAGAACACAGCAUGUCCAAGGGGGCUGAGGCUGAAGGGCAGGCCAUCCCCCAGCGAUUACAUUCGGAUUACCGACUUAAUCUGCUUUGGUAUUUGACCGCCAGCCUAACCACCCCAGGCUGCAUUUGGAGGAUAUUGAGCACUUUCAUCCCCAAGCACUUCACUGGCUUUAUAAAUGACCCACUCGAUUCCCUUCGGCCUCCUCUGGGAUGGGACAUGGCAGCUGUUUAAUUGCCACAUAGCAAUGUUGCAGUGUUUUAAGGCAGAAAAGAAGAAUCCUGCAUCCAGUUGAAGCUGCAGGGAACAUUUAGGGAAGGGGAAUGUAAUUAUCCACAUUGGAAGUGGGCCAGGGUUUGGAGCUUUGGGGAAAGAGGCCUUUAGGACUUCUACUUUCCAGCCCACCUGAAAGAUGGGGCCUCCUUUCAGCAGUCUGGGACAUCAGCCUGCUUCCUGCUGAUUUAGGAAAAAGCCCCCAGGCGCCACCUCCUUUAUAUAUUCCCCAUCAGACUCUUCACCGGGGUGGAAAGUCUCUUUUCCAAGGUCUGGCUGGGGCUCAGCUGGGAAGAUAUGACAGCGUCCCGGGAAGCUGCCUCACACCAGUUUGGGUUUAACAUAUAAUCAAAUCAGAGUGACAGCAGAUGGAAACAGUCUUCUGUUGCCGCAGGAGCCGUCCUUGAGUUCAGAAACAAAGACGGGGGCAAGAAAGACAAGACAAAGUGUGCAUUUGUACAUGUGUGUUCACACCCAUGCACUUGUGCAUAGGAAAAAUAAGAAGGACUUCCCCAAAAUCUUUUAUUGGGUCUUAUCUCUAGAGGGAAUGGGAAAGGAGACUUUCUUCUACAUUCUAACAAAGAAUUUAAUUCUCAAGGUGUUUAAACAAAAAAUAAAGGUGAAGCAGCCAGA